AGACCCCUCGGUCUUGCUAUGUCGAGCUCACCCGUGAAGCGUCAGAGGAUGGAGUCCGCGCUGGACCAGCUCAAGCAGUUCACCACCGUGGUGGCCGACACGGGCGACUUCCACGCCAUCGACGAGUACAAGCCCCAGGAUGCUACCACCAACCCGUCCCUGAUCCUGGCCGCAGCACAGAUGCCCGCUUACCAGGAGCUGGUGGAGGAGGCGAUUGCCUAUGGCCGGAAGCUGGGCGGGUCACAAGAGGACCAGAUUAAAAAUGCUAUUGAUAAACUUUUUGUGUUGUUUGGAGCAGAAAUACUAAAGAAGAUUCCGGGCCGAGUAUCCACAGAAGUAGACGCAAGGCUCUCCUUUGAUAAAGAUGCGAUGGUGGCCAGAGCCAGGCGGCUCAUCGAGCUCUACAAGGAAGCUGGGAUCAGCAAGGACCGAAUUCUUAUAAAGCUGUCAUCAACCUGGGAAGGAAUUCAGGCUGGAAAGGAGCUCGAGGAGCAGCACGGCAUCCACUGCAACAUGACGUUACUCUUCUCCUUCGCCCAGGCUGUGGCCUGUGCCGAGGCGGGUGUGACCCUCAUCUCCCCAUUUGUUGGGCGCAUCCUUGAUUGGCAUGUGGCAAACACCGACAAGAAAUCCUAUGAGCCCCUGGAAGACCCUGGGGUAAAGAGUGUCACUAAAAUCUACAACUACUACAAGAAGUUUAGCUACAAAACCAUUGUCAUGGGCGCCUCCUUCCGCAACACGGGCGAGAUCAAAGCACUGGCCGGCUGUGACUUCCUCACCAUCUCACCCAAGCUCCUGGGAGAGCUGCUGCAGGACAACGCCAAGCUGGUGCCUGUGCUCUCAGCCAAGGCGGCCCAAGCCAGUGACCUGGAAAAAAUCCACCUGGAUGAGAAGUCUUUCCGUUGGUUGCACAACGAGGACCAGAUGGCUGUGGAGAAGCUCUCUGACGGGAUCCGCAAGUUUGCCGCUGAUGCAGUGAAGCUGGAGCGGAUGCUGACAGAACGAAUGUUCAAUGCAGAGAAUGGAAAGUAGCGCAUCCCUGAGGCUGGACUCCAGAUCUGCACCGCCGGCCAGCUGGGAUCUGACUGCACGUGGCUUCUGAUGAAUCUUGCGUUUUUUACAAAUUGGAGCAGGGACAGAUCAUAGAUUUCUGAUUUUAUGUAAAAUUUUGCCUAAUACAUUAAAGCAGUCACUUUUCC